GCUAGUCUCUCGGUCUGGCUCUCUCUCCGACGGGACUUAGCAACUUCUUAUUUCUCAGCCCCUUGUCCAUUUUUUUUUUUCCAUCCUUUGCCAUGAAUUGGAUUGACAGAGGCGGGGGAGGCUUUGCUUUCUGCCCCAGGGAAUGGCGAUUCGCGUCCUGGGGCCGUGCCGGGGAGAAUCGGCCGAGGAGAAAGAAAGAGUGAUAGAAAAAGAGCUGCAGGAAGGAGGAGAAGGGAGACCUCCAUCUGCCGCGGGCCCGGCGCGCUGCAGCGCAGCGCAGCGCCGAGCUGCGCCUCGGAAUGGCCCGGAGCCCGCCCUGCGCCCCCGGCUCCUCCAGCGUCAGCGGCUCCUGCGCGCGGGAUGCAUUGGGCAAUUUUUGAAAUCCUGAAGUAGGAAGAGACCCCGGAGGAUAUAAGUCGGGGGUGGGGGUGGAGCAGAGAAUCUGUGAAAGAUAUUCAAAGAGAGAAAAGGGGAAUCCUGAUCGUUUCUGCCCGUGCUUGUUUUCAACUUGAGCGUGCUAGCCUUUAACUUGAAGAAGUCUCAUUGGAGCAUCUAGCAUUCUCCAGGAGUUAUUCGAAAGCUGAAACUUUCAGUGGAUUGUGGGCCUGGGGAGAAGAAGGAUUCCGAGGGUGGAAUUGGGAAGAGCGUGCGUGCGUGUGUGUGUGUGUGUGUGUGCGCGCGCGCGCGUGGGUCGGGGCGGGGGCGUCGGGGGGCCACUGGGAAUUCAGUGAAGAGGGCACCCUAUACCAUGGCAGUGCCCGGCGACGCUGCACGAGUCAGGGACAAGCCCGUCCACAGUGGGGUGAGUCAAGCCCCCACGGCGGGCCGGGACUGCCACCAUCGUGCGGACCCCGCAUCGCCGCGGGACUCGGGCUGCCGUGGCUGCUGGGGAGACCUGGUGCUGCAGCCGCUCCGGAGCUCUCGGAAACUUUCCUCCGCGCUGUGCGCGGGCUCCCUGUCCUUUCUGCUGGCGCUGCUGGUGAGGCUGGUCCGCGGGGAGGUCGGCUGUGACCUGGAGCAGUGUAAGGAGGCGGCGGCGGCGGAGGAGGAGGAAGCAGCCCCGGGAGCAGAAGGGGGCGUCUUCCCGGGGCCUCGGGGAGGUGCUCCCGGGGGCGGUGCGCGGCUCAGCCCCUGGCUGCAGCCCUCGGCGCUGCUCUUCAGUCUCCUGUGUGCCUUCUUCUGGAUGGGCUUGUACCUCCUGCGCGCCGGGGUGCGCCUGCCUCUGGCUGUCGCGCUGCUGGCCGCCUGCUGCGGGGGGGAAGCGCUCGUCCAGAUUGGGCUGGGCGUCGGGGAGGAUCACUUACUCUCACUCCCCGCCGCGGGGGUGGUGCUCAGCUGCUUGGCCGCCGCGACAUGGCUGGUGCUGAGGCUGAGGCUGGGCGUCCUCAUGAUCGCCUUGACUAGCGCGGUCAGGACCGUGUCCCUCAUUUCCUUAGAGAGGUUCAAGGUCGCCUGGAGACCUUACCUGGCGUACCUGGCCGGCGUGCUGGGGAUCCUCUUGGCCAGGUACGUGGAACAAAUCUUGCCGCAGUCCGCGGAGGCGGCUCCAAGGGAGCAUUUGGGGUCCCAGCUGAUUGCUGGGACCAAGGAAGAUAUCCCGGUGUUUAAGAGGAGGAGGCGGUCCAGCUCCGUCGUGUCCGCCGAGAUGUCCGGCUGCAGCAGCAAGUCCCAUCGGAGGACCUCCCUGCCCUGUAUACCGAGGGAACAGCUUCUAGAGGCUGCCCAAGUUCCUUGGCUUGCGACCCUCUUUCUCCAGUUUCAAAGCUGGCAAAGCUCAUGGGGCAUUCAGAAUGGGACCACAAACGAGGGCCAAGAGGAUCACAGUCUUCAGGAACCAGUAUUACUGUGGACAUCGCCGUCAUGGGCGAGGCCCACGGCCUCAUUACCGACCUCCUGGCAGACCCUUCUCUUCCACCAAACGUGUGCACAUCCUUGAGAGCCGUGAGCAACUUGCUCAGCACACAGCUCACCUUCCAGGCCAUUCACAAGCCCAGAGUGAAUCCCGUCACUUCGCUCAGUGAAAACUAUACCUGUUCUGACUCUGAAGAGAGCUCUGAAAAAGACAAGCUUGCUAUUCCAAAGCGCCUGAGAAGGAGUUUGCCUCCUGGCUUGUUGAGACGAGUUUCUUCCACUUGGACCACCACCACCUCGGCCACAGGUCUACCCACCUUGGAGCCUGCACCAGUACGGAGAGACCGCAGCACCAGCAUCAAACUGCAGGAAGCACCUUCAUCCAGUCCUGAUUCUUGGAAUAAUCCAGUGAUGAUGACCCUCACCAAAAGCAGAUCCUUUACUUCAUCCUAUGCUAUUUCUGCAGCUAACCAUGUAAAGGCUAAAAAGCAAAGUCGACCAGGUGCCCUCGCUAAAAUUUCACCUCUUUCAUCGCCCUGCUCCUCACCUCUCCAAGGGACUCCUGCCAGCAGCCUGGUCAGCAAAAUUUCUGCAGUGCAGUUUCCAGAAUCUGCUGACACAACUGCCAAACAAAGCCUAGGUUCUCACAGGGCCUUAACUUACACUCAGAGUGCCCCAGACCUAUCCCCUCAAAUCCUGACUCCACCUGUUAUAUGUAGCAGCUGUGGCAGACCAUAUUCCCAAGGGAAUCCUGCUGAUGAGCCCCUGGAGAGAAGUGGGGUAGCCACUCGGACACCAAGUAGAACAGAUGACACUGCUCAAGUUACCUCUGAUUAUGAAACCAAUAACAACAGUGACAGCAGUGACAUUGUACAGAAUGAAGAUGAAACAGAGUGCCUGAGAGAGCCUCUGAGGAAAGCAUCGGCUUGCAGCACCUAUGCUCCUGAGACCAUGAUGUUUCUGGACAAACCAAUUCUUGCUCCCGAACCUCUUGUCAUGGAUAACCUGGACUCAAUUAUGGAGCAGCUAAAUACUUGGAAUUUUCCAAUUUUUGAUUUAGUGGAAAAUAUAGGAAGAAAAUGUGGCCGUAUUCUUAGUCAGGUAUCUUACAGACUUUUUGAAGACAUGGGCCUCUUUGAAGCUUUUAAAAUUCCAAUUAGGGAAUUUAUGAAUUAUUUUCAUGCUUUGGAGAUUGGAUAUAGGGAUAUUCCUUAUCAUAACAGAAUCCAUGCCACUGAUGUUUUACAUGCUGUUUGGUAUCUUACUACACAGCCUAUUCCAGGCCUCUCAACUGUGAUUAAUGAUCAUGGUUCAACCAGUGAUUCAGAUUCUGACAGUGGAUUUACACAUGGACAUAUGGGAUAUGUAUUCUCAAAAACGUAUAAUGUGACAGAUGAUAAAUACGGAUGUCUGUCUGGGAAUAUCCCUGCCUUGGAGUUGAUGGCGCUGUAUGUGGCUGCAGCCAUGCACGAUUAUGAUCAUCCAGGAAGGACUAAUGCUUUCCUGGUUGCAACUAGUGCUCCUCAGGCGGUGCUAUAUAACGAUCGUUCAGUUUUGGAGAAUCAUCACGCAGCUGCUGCAUGGAAUCUUUUCAUGUCCCGGCCAGAGUAUAACUUCUUAAUUAACCUUGACCAUGUGGAAUUUAAGCAUUUCCGUUUCCUUGUCAUUGAAGCAAUUUUGGCCACUGACCUGAAGAAACACUUUGACUUCGUAGCCAAAUUUAAUGGCAAGGUAAAUGAUGAUGUUGGAAUAGAUUGGACCAAUGAAAAUGAUCGUCUACUGGUUUGUCAAAUGUGUAUAAAGUUGGCUGAUAUCAAUGGUCCAGCUAAAUGUAAAGAACUCCAUCUUCAGUGGACAGAUGGUAUUGUCAAUGAAUUUUAUGAACAGGGUGAUGAAGAGGCCAGCCUUGGAUUACCCAUAAGCCCCUUCAUGGAUCGUUCUGCUCCUCAGCUGGCCAACCUUCAGGAAUCCUUCAUCUCUCACAUUGUGGGGCCUCUGUGCAACUCCUAUGAUUCAGCAGGACUAAUGCCUGGAAAAUGGGUGGAAGACAGCGAUGAGUCAGGAGAUACUGAUGACCCAGAAGAAGAGGAGGAAGAAGCACCAGCACCAAAUGAAGAGGAAACCUGUGAAAAUAAUGAAUCUCCAAGCAAGUACCAGAUGCCUCUAGCCUACCGUCUUGAAGACACCCUCCAAGACAAGUUUCUUAAAGGAGGUAUGCUAAGAAAAGAAGACUUUCAAAAGGAGAAAAAUCUACUGCCAAAUAACUCAGCACCUCUUACAGAACCACAAGAUGUGGAAGAAAGUCAUUGAAGAGGAGCAACGGUUGGCAGGCAUAGAAAAUCAAUCCCUGGACCAGACCCCUCAGUCGCACUCUUCAGAACAGAUCCAGGCUAUCAAGGAAGAAGAAGAAGAGAAAGGGAAACCAAGAGGCGAGGAGAUACCAACCCAAAAGCCAGACCAGUGACAAUGGAUAGAAUGGGCUGUGUUUCCAAACAGAUUGACUUGUCAAAGACUCUCUUCAAGCCAGCACAACAUUUAGACACAACACUGUAGAAAUUUGAGAUGGGCAAAUGGCUAUUGCAUUUUGGGAUUCUUCGCAUUUUGUGUGUAUAUUUUUACAGUGAGGUACAUUGUUAAAAACUUUUUGCUCAAAGAAGCUUUCACAUUGCAACACCAGCUUCUAAGGAUUUUUUAAGGAGGGAAUAUAUAUGUGUGUGUGUAUAUAAGCUCCCACAUAGAUACAUGUAAAACAUAUUCACACCCAUGCACGCACACACAUACACACUGAAGGCCACGAUUGCUGGCUCCACAAUUUAGUAACAUUUAUAUUAAGAUAUAUAUAUAGUGGUCACUGUGAUAUAAUAAAUCAUAAAGGAAACCAAAUCACAAAGGAGAUGGUGUGGCUUAGCAAGGAAACAGUGCAGGAAAUGUAGGUUACCAACUAAGCAGCUUUUGCUCUUAGUACUGAGGGAUGAAAGUUCCAGAGCAUUAUUUGAAUUCUGAUACAUCCUGCCAACACUGUGUGUGUGUGUGUGUGUGUGUGUGUGUGUGUGUGUGUGUGUGAAAGAGAGACAGAAGGGAAUGGUUUGAGAGGGUGCUUGUGUGCAUGUGUGUGCAUAUGUAAAGAGAUUUUUGUGGUUUAAGUAACUCAGAAUAGCUGUAGCAAAUGACUGAAUACAUGUGAACAAACAGAAGGAAGUUCACUCUGGAGUGUCUUUGGGAGGCAGCCAUUCCAAAUGCCCUCCUCCAUUUAGCUUCAAUAAAGGGCCUUUUGCUGAUGGAGGGCACUCAAGGGCUGGGUGAGAGGGCCACGUGUUUGGUAUUACAUUACUGCUAUGCACCACUUGAAGGAGCUCUAUCACCAGCCUCAAACCCGAAAGACUGAGGCAUUUUCCAGUCUACUUGCCUAAUGAAUGUAUAGGAACUGUCUAUGAGUAUGGAUGUCACUCAACUAAGAUCAAAUCACCAUUUAAGGGGAUGGCAUUCUUUAUACCUAAACACCUAAGAGCUGAAGUCAGGUCUUUUAAUCAGGUUAGAAUUCUAAAUGAUGCCAGAGAAGGCUUGGGAAAUUGUACUUCAGCGUGAUAGCCUGUGUCUUCUUAAUUUGCUGCAAAAUAUGUGGUAGAGAAAGAAAAGGAAACAGAAAAAUCACUCUGGGUUAUAUAGCAAGAGAUGAAGGAGAAUAUUUCAACACAGGGUUUUUGUGUUGACAUAGGAAAAGCCUGAUUCUUGGCAACUGUUGUAGUUUGUCUUUCAGGGGUGAAGGUCCCACUGACAACCCCUGUUGUGGUGUUCCACACGCUGUUUGUUGGGGUAGCUUCCAUCGGCAGUCUGGCCCAUUGUCAGUCAUGCUUCUUCUGGCCGGGGAGAUUAUAGAGAGAUUGUUUGAAGAUUGGGUUAUUAUUGAAAGUCUUUUUUUUUGUUUGUUUUGUUUUGGUUUGUUUGUUUAUCUACACUUGUUUAUGCUGUGAGCCAAACCUCUAUUUAAAAAGUUGAUACUCACUUUCAAUAUUUUAUUUCAUAUUAUUAUAUAUGUCAUGAUAGUUAUCUUGAUGUAAAUAUGAAGAUUUUUUUGUUUCUGUAGAUAGUAAACUCUUUUUUUAAAAAAGGAAAAGGGAAACAUUUUUAUAAAGUUAUAUUUUAAUCACCAUUUUUAUACAUUGUAGUUCUCUCCAAGCCCAGUAAGAGAAUGAUGAUUCAUUUGCAUGGAGGUCGAUGGACAACCAAUCAUCUACCUUUUCUAAUUUAAAUGAUAAUCUGAUAUAGUUUUAUUGCCAGUUAAAUGAGGAUGCUGCAAAGCAUGUUUUUUCACUAGUAACUUUUGCUAACUGAAUGAAUUCUGGGUCCAUAUCUCCCAGAUGAAAAACUGUUAACCAAUACCAUAUUUUAUAGUUGGUGUCCAUUUCUUUCCAACACUGUUUGUUAUGAUUCUUCCUUGAGUACUUAUAUACAGACCUGCUCAUUAUCUAAACAAUCUUACCUUCUAAGUAAACCUUGAUUGUGAUUUCCAGUUUUUAUUUUCUCUGACGUAGUAGAAAGGAAUGUUUACAUUAAAAAUACUUUUGUUUCUCAUAAAUGGAUAUUGUACUCCCCCCUUUCAAAGCAUUAUUUUACAAUAAUUCAUGGCAUUUUAAAAAAUAAGGCAAAGAUAAUACGACAAAAAAUAUACAUGGUUUCAAGGCAAAUUCUCCAAUAAGUUGGAAAAUGUAAAAAGGAUCAAGUGGAUGCAGCCUCUACCUAAAUAAUUAAAAUAUAUUUCAGUAUAUUUCUGAAUUAACACCAGGUCUUCAUUAUUUAGAACUUACUAAAUUGUUUUCAUUUUCUUAGUUUUACCUGUGUAUCUCCAUGUUUGCAAAAAUUACUAUAAGUCAAAUUUUGCCAGUGAAUUUAACUAUUUUUCUUUCCUUGCAAUUAAGGGGAAAAAAGCAUUUAUCUUAUCUUCUCAUACCCCUUGCAUCUAAGUACUUAGCAAAGUCAAUAUUUUCCCAUUUUCCAAAUGCGUCCAUCUCUAACAUAAAUAUUAAUUGAACAUAGAGCUAUGUUUGGAGUGAGUGGACUGGCAGGACAGUUGGAAGUCCAUCACAGUCUAUUGACAGUUUCAUCAAAGCUGUAUAGUCCAACUAGUGGGGCAGCUUGGCUACUAUGGUGGAAGUCUCAGCAAACUGCCUGGUUUUGUUUGUUUGUUUUGUUUUAAGGUACAGGAAAUAAGAGGAAUAAUAGUGGCCAAAGCAAUUAGAACAUCUUCAUUCCAGAACUGUGUUCAGCAAUCCAGGCAGAUUGAUACAUUUUUCUUUAAAAAUAAAUUGCUAUUACAGCUAGACGUCAAUUGGGAUAAAUAAAGGGAUGAAGAUCCACUAAGUUUGUGACUUUCAUACACACCCAGUACAUCUCAAAGGAUGCUAAGGGACAUUUUCUGCCAGUAGAGUUCUCCCCCUUUUUGGUGACAGCAAUAUUAUUAUGUUCACAUCUAACUCCAGAGCUUACUUCCUGUGGUGCCAAUGUAUUUGUUGCAAUUUACUACAUUUUUAUAUGAGCCUAUUUAUAGGUGCCAUUAAACUCAGGUCUUUCAAAUGAAAGAGUUUCUAGCCCACUUAGGGAAAAAGAUAAUUGUUUAGAAAACCAUAAAAUCAAUGGUAGGAAAAGUUGGAACUGGUUACCUGGAUGCCAUGGUUCUCUGUUAAAUAAAGUAAGAGACCAGGUGUAUUCUGAGUGUCAUCAGUGUUAUUUUCAGCAUGCUAAUAAAUGUCUUUCCGGUUAUAUAUCUAUCUAAAUUAACCUUUAAAAUAUUGGUUUCCUUGAUAAAAGCACCACUUUUGCUUUUGUUAGCUGUAAUAUUUUUUGUCAUUUAGAUAAGACCUGGUUUGGCUCUCAAUAAAAGAUGAAGACAGUAGCUCUGUACAGGGAUAUAUCUAUAUUAGUCUUCAUCUGAUGAAUGAAGAAAUUUUCUCAUAUUAUGUUCAAGAAAGUAUUUACUUCCUAAAAAUAGAAUUCCCGAUUCUGUCUAUUUUGGUUGAAUACCAGAACAAAUCUUUCCGUUGCAAUCCCAGUAAAACGAAAGAAAAGGAAUAUCUUACAGACUGUUCAUAUUAGAUGUAUGUAGACUGUUAAUUUGCAAUUUCCCCAUAUUUCCUGCCUAUCUUACCCAGAUAACUUUCUUUGAAGGUAAAAGCUGUGCAAAAGGCAUGAGACUCAGGCCUACUCUUUGUUUAAAUGAUGGAAAAAUAUAAAUUAUUUUCUAAGUAAUAAAAGUAUAAAAAUUAUCAUUAUAAAUAAAGUCUAAAGUUUGAAAUUAUUAAUUUAUAAAAGUGAACUAAUUGUGUGAUUAUCAAAUCCUGAUUAAUGAGAAGUGAAUAAUCUAAAAAUCAUUUAUAUUCUACUGUGGGAGGUAUUCUUGGUGCUUCCAUGUCAGUAUCGGGCUCUCCAUUGUCCUCAUCAUUUAUAGUACUUCUAAAAUAAUAAUGGAAACCUCAAUAAGGGUCUUGUCCUCUUCUGUCAUCCUAACCCUGAUUCUAGUUUAAUGCCUUUCCUGACUUAUAUGCCAUUUGUAAAUAAACUUCCUUUCAAACUGUUAGAACGCUCCAAUAAAACAAAGUUCUAUGAACUUUCAUAGUCUAGAAAAACCAACAAGAUCCCCCUUAUUUAGAGAUUAUUAGCUAAUGUGUGAAAGAAAUAUCAAUAGAAGUUCAAAUGCUAAUAGCUCAAUUCCAGAUAAUUGAAAGCUAAAAUAUCUAUGUACUUUGAAGCCAAACUGAGUUUAUUUCAUUGAUCGAACAAGCAGCAACACAUUUUAUGACCAUUGUCCUAGGUCGUUUGUGUCUUUAUGAAUUUGCUGAUAUUGUCAGUCCAUUUUUUAAAUCUUCAACAAAAUUCAAUUUUAAGAUUAAGAAAUCAGCAAUUUUAGGUAAAGAAUAUUCCAAGAUUAAAUUGUUCUUUUUAAGAAAUAUAUCAGUUUUAGGUCCUAUGUUCACACAUCAAUUUGUUCAUCUGGAAGAUAUUCAAAUUCUUAUUGGGAAUGAAUUACACUACAAACAAUGAGUUGAGCUAAAAACUAUACAUAACUUAAAUUGAGAUUUGCAUACGUAUUUGUGUGUUUCACACCAAAGACCCAUGCUCAGAGAAUGGUAACAUAUUUUCCAGUCUAUGUUAUGCACCAUGGAUGUUAGGCAAUGUGUGCUAUUGCCAACACAUGGUAUUUGUUGAAAUACAUGUUGCUUUGACCUUACCUAAUGGUGCUUUUACCUAACUUGAAGUGCUUUUUGUGUUCCCACCAGCAAAUCAUUCUAACAGCAGGCUAACAAUGGUGAAGUAAAAUGAACAUUUUUGGGCCGGGCGCAGUGGCUCACGCCUGUAAUCCCAGCACUUUGGGAGGCCAAGGCUGGUGGAUCACCUGAGGUCGGGAGUUCGACACCAGCCUGACCAACACGGAGAAACCCCGUCUUUACUAAAAAUACAAAAUGAUUCAGGUGUGGUGGCGCAUGUCUGUAAUCCCAGCUACCCAGGAGGCUGAGGCAGAAUCGCUUGAACCUGGGAGGCAGAGGUUAUGGUGAGCUGAGAUUGCACCAUUGCACUCCAGCCUGGGCAACAGGAGUUAAAUUUUGCCUCAAAAAAAAAAAAAAAAAAAAAAAGAACAUUUUUUGGCAAAAUAUGAAGACACGAAACUGAAGAUAAAGGCUUCAUUUCCAUAGUGGAAAUCAGUGUUUACCUGCUGAUUCAAAAAUACUGACCUAGUAUCAGUGUAGGUAAGACCAUAAAAUACAGUGUAUAGAAUUAUAUAUAAAUGGAAAACAAAAUUAGCUUUUGACAUAUGUUUAAGUCUCUAAAAGGAAUCCACAUUUUCUUUCCAGAUACAGCUAGUUUUUCUCCACAUGUUUUUAAGGUUGAUUUCCUUGACACACAUUGGUAUCCUUGGGUUUCUGCUUCCUUGAAAAGUUGUGGAGCACAGAAGAAAAGCCUUCUCUUUACAGAUAAAAAAUGUUGAACAUGUUCAUGUUCUGACAAUGAAGCAAUGAUUUCCUCAUUGCUUUGCAUUAAGAAGUGGUUCUUUAGUUAUGCAAAUAAUUCAAUAACCAAAAAUGCUUCAAAGAGUAAUAAUAAAUCACCAUAGGUAAGUAUUCUCAAGAAUGUUUAAAUUUGGUUUAUUUUCUUGAAGCAAAGUUAUUUAAUUUUUUAAUUUUUAACUUAAAAUGAAACCCACAAAAUGACAUUCCGUGGUACUGAGUAUUUUCACAUAAUCAGAACUGUAAACUACUGAUUAUUUUCAUAUACUCAGAGGCUGAAUAUUUUGAUAUAAUAAGAACUAGUAUCAUAUAACAGAAAACUAGAAAGAAGGUUUAAUUCUUUUUCUAAUAUUCUACAAGCCUCAUGGGGAAAAUGUUUUAUGAAGGAUUCAAAUACAUUAGAUAAAAAUUAGUGUCAAUAAUUUAACUUUGUACAAAUUAUAGUCUGAGAUCUUCUGAGUUUUCCUAAGACAAAGGAGUGUAUUAUCCAGCAAUUUAUUGUUUUGUGUUGUUAUAAAAUAAAUGUUCUAUUAAUGUAUAUUUUAUUUUACUAAGUUCUAACACAAAAGGCCAAAUACUUAUCUUUCCUACUAAGAAAAAUUAAACCUUACUAAUCUUGACUUUCACAGAUGAAACACUGACCAGUCAAUAAACAACAGCCACUGCAUUAAUCUGCCCAGCAUGAUCAGAUAGUAGGUUAGAAUUUGAAAUUCAUUAAUAAAAAAUUAAUAACAAAACUUUGUAAGCCUUAAUGGUUUAAUAUUUCCGUGUCAUUGAAAGUUCCUAUUUCAAAUUAAACAAACUACAGCAGGAUAUUUUUCCUUUCCUGUUUCAAAACAAAAACCAGAUGAAGAAAAAACAAAGACAAACUCAUAGGAGGAAAGCAUGGCUUCUCUUCAAUUAUACUUCUCUUACUCAAUAUUAGUAACCAAAAAAUAAGCAGAAAUUCUCCUCUGCCAUAAUUAAAAGAAAGAAUGGCCUUCGACUUAAGUUCUAGUUCCUCAAGCCUGCUUUCCUUGUAAAGUCCAUGGUACUAAGAAGCAAAAAAUGCAGAGCUGUGGAUUGGGAGUGAACACUACAUAAAAUUUGCAGGGUAUCCCAGGACACCCCUCAGUCUUUAAUACAAACCAAUUUAGUUACUCUGGAGUGAAAUGACUUGUGGAUACACUGUUCAACCAUGACUUCCUUUAUGACAAGGAGCACUUAUACAUGUUUCCAAAUGUGAAUUAGCCCUUGAAUUAGUUUGAAAACUGCUACUUGAAUAACUUUUGAAGAGAAAGAUUUUCUUUCCGGUAAUUUUACUCCCUAAAAAAGGCAAAAUACUCAGAUGUUCAAUGUGAAAUUACAAAUAGUUGUUUGAAGUAUAUAUACUUCAAUAAAUAGUUCUUUGUGUAUAUAAAGUGUUGGUUCAUAGCAGUUUCCUUGUCCCUUUUCUUUUUAAAAUUCCCAACUGAUUAUGGGUCAAAAACUCCAUCUUAUAUCAGCGAUGAUUUCAUUUUAACUAUUUAUAAGGAUAAUUUAGUAUUAUAGUAUUGCUAACUUUAAUAAUUCUACCAUAUCUAUAUAUUACCUGUUAGUGAGGUUUUAAUGGCUUUACUUAAUACAUAUUUGUUCAUCAGCUUAAAAAAUCACUAAAUUUUUUAUACUCUGUAAAAUAUUUGCAUGGGAAUUUUAGCUUAUUAUGUUUGCUUAACUGGUGUUUUUUUCACUUAUGACUGUCAGUUUAUGUCUUAAUGUAUUCUCACAGAAGAAUGCAUACCAUUUUUGUUCCAACAAGAACAAUCUGUUAGUUGAUAAGCACUGGUAAUAAAUAUCACUGAACCCACCCACCCCCUGAUAUUUCUUCCUCAAGUUUUCUAUCAUGCAAAUCACAAAAUGAAAAUUGGUGCUUUUACAAAUAUUUGAAAGCUCUCAAUGCAAAAUAAUAAAAAUGAGAUUCUCCCUGGCUUUCUAUAAUAUAUUAGGAUAUGUGACUGAAGGAAAUUUAAUCUGAAUUUAGAGUGUUUUAGGUUUUGGUUGGUUUGAAUAAUUUGAUUUGCAUUUUGGUAUUAAAAUGUGCUCUGAUUUCUGCGGGCAUUUGUUCUGACCAGUCAUUACCUCUUCCCAACAGAAAAAAAAAAAAAAAAAAAAAAACUGGCAUUGGCAAGUUUUAAUUAAUAUGGCCCAAAAAUUUGACCUUGAAGGAUAUUUGUAAACCAGAGAGUAUUUAAUUAACUAAAUUUACUGUUUCUGAAAAGCAAUAUUUUCAAAUAACUGCCAACCAAAGUGACACUAUAGGGAUGUCAUUUGUACAUGACAAUUUUUAACAAUGUAAUUCUUACCACUCUCGACAGACCUGAAUAUGUUUACUAAUAACUUUGCCAAAUUUUUCAACUUCUAGAAAAACAAGAGUGAGUCUUUUGAACUUCAUCAUUUUGCAAUUGAAAUAAAUCUUGUCCUUUCACCUAUAUCUUCCAUUUAAUAUAUGUAGCAAUACUUAGUAUCAUCCCAUCACAAGUAUUGUUAGGCGACUUAGUGGCGGAGAAAUGUUUGUAAAAAGUAGAAUCUGUACAGAAAAAAAACUAGAUCAAUUGUAUUUAUUUUUAUUAUUUUUUAGCUUAGAUACUAUGUUGAUGCUCCCUUUUUGCCAGAAUUACUGGAAGUGCCUCUUGGUUUUAUAUAUAUAAUAUAUAAAUAUUACAGUAAAUAUAUACUCAAAAUUAUUAAAAUUAUGUCCUAGAUUAUCUAUGUCGAUGUUAUGAGUGAAGAUAAUGUAUAAUAUAAAAAUAAUUCUGCAGUA